UACCAGAUUCUAUUUGUUAAAACUGAGUCACUCAGUACAGCUCCCAUGCAAAGUUUGCUUUUAGUUCUCAUUGUGAGAUCACAAGUGGAGGCUCCAACCAGUCCAGAAGUUCCUUUCUAUGGGGAAGCUGUGGCAGCAAGGCCGUGAAGAGAGUCUGACUUAAUUGCAAUGGGAGAGAAGGAGAUGUGAUCAGGGAGGAGAACACAGAAGACUUCUAAGAUACCAGUAAUAUUUGAUCUGUUCUUAAAUCAGGAGGAGAUUCAGGUACACCAUGUGUUUAUUAUUCCAUAAAAUCCAUAGAUGUGUUUUAUAUACUUUUUGUUUAUAUGAUUUUUAAAAAAUUAAGGGAACAAAUCUUAUCCUCAAGGAGAGACGUAAUGAUGGAGGAAGGAAUAUAGAAGGAGACAAAAAGGAGGGAGUCUUGAUGAAAAGGGAGAUGGGAGGCAGCUUUUAACACCAGACAGGGUCCUGUGAUGCAGAGGUGAUUGUGCCAUCCCAUAAAGUCCCAGGGCACUGUCUGCCAAUGAGACCACCAACUUGCUUGCCCUAAAUGGCCACAUCCCCUAAACGGCCCUCCUGCCAUUGUCUGUGCUCAGAAAACCCUCAGUUUCUGCCUCUUACCUGCCAGGGUGGUGCCACAUCCCACCCCCAUCAUUGAGCUUGCCUCAUGUGUCUCAGCACAGUCUUUUACAGCAAAAAUGCAUGUCACCUCCUCCUAAAGGCUUUCCGUGGCCCACCCACCCAGAUUCCUCCUUUAUUGUGCAGACUCUUUCCUAACCCACACCUCAUCUUAAUUUAUUUGCCUUCAAUUCUGGGCGGCGGUGUUGGGGAGGGUCUCAAUUUUCCCAUGUAUUUCCCAGUGUUUAUUGAAUACAUGAGGCCAUACUCUUCUAGUCUCUCUGCUUCUCAUGCUAGGAACUGAACCGACCAGCCUAUACUUUAAGGCUUGUUAUUUCACUGACUAAGGAAAGGCUACUUAAGAGGGCAAGCUCAGACAUACAUAAUCUGGAGUGGAUCUUCCAUGGGAAAACACGUAUAUAACAGAAAUUAUUGGCAAAACUAUAAGUAUGGUCUACAGAAUCCUGAAUAAUUUCUACUUAAACGUCCCAAUAUCAACUCUCUAUUUUGCUAUUGACAUAAUCUUAUUUGAGAGGCAAAAAAUUUUAAAAAUUAUAUCAUCUUUUUAAUUUCUAAGCCCCAGAACAAGACAAUUGGCAGCAUUUUUUUCAUGUCAUUUUGCUACAUUCUACAUAAUGUUAAGUUGAGGUUAGGGAUUUUCAUUUGUGGAGGAAGCUCUUACAUUUAGUUUAAUGAAUCAUAAUUUUUUUAAUGGAGAAGGAACAAAAUACCUCAUUGAUUUUUCUAUGAGUGGAGUUAAUACACACAGCGGAGAAAUCUCUUUGUUAAUUCUACACUCUGCCUCUGAUUGACACCUCUGCAAACAAAGAUAAAGUAGAUAAAACAUGAAUAAUUCCAGGAAACUUAUGCCCCAGAAUACAGAAUAAUUUUGCAUACAUAUGAAUAGUAGGGCAAUUCUAUCAAAUGAUUCUUUUCUAAUUCUUUAUGGAUGUACAUAAUGAAAUAUUCAGAACUACCACAACAUUUAGAAUAAGAUAGAGCCUAACAAUUUAUUGUUGAAUUAAUGAAGAUCGGUUAAUUAAUCCAUGUUUUACAUCAGCUUUCUUUGCCCUCAACCAGGAAGUCAGAGGCACCAAUGUGAGGUUCCACCUGCUUUCCAGCACAUUCUUGGUUUCCUCACUUCUGCUAGACAACGUUUGAUCAGAAGGAACAGGGAACGAGAAGGAGCUGCUGGAUGACAAUAAGCCUGGGAAAGGGAGGCUGGGUGAGCAGAGACAGAAAAGAAACACCUACCUGCUGUGACCUCACAAACACCCAGGCUGAGUUUUGAUAAGACAGGUUGAAUCACACUGGGGUGACAGCCUCAUCCCUCCAGAUGCUGGUCAACCUCUGGGGCCCAAAGAAGACCAUCAGCUUCCUGGGAUGCUCUGUCCAGCUCUUCAUCUUCCUGUCCCUGGGGACCACUGAGUGCAUCCUCCUGACAGUGAUGGCCUUUGACCGAUACGUGGCUGUCUGCCAGCCCCUCCACUAUGCCACCAUCAUCCACCCCCGCCUGUGCUGGCAGCUGGCAUCUGUGGCCUGGGUUAUGAGUCUGGUUCAAUCGAUAGUCCAGACACCAUCCACCCUCCACUUGCCCUUCUGUCCCCACCAGCAGAUAGAUGACUUUUUAUGUGAGGUCCCAUCUCUGAUUCGACUCUCCUGUGGAGAUACCUCCUACAAUGAAAUCCAGUUGGCUGUGUCCAGUGUCAUCUUCGUGGUUGUGCCUCUCAGCCUCAUCCUUGCCUCUUAUGGAGCCACUGCCCAGGCAGUGCUGAGGAUUAACUCUGCCACAGCAUGGAGAAAGGCCUUUGGGACCUGCUCCUCCCAUCUCACUGUGGUCACCCUCUUCUACAGCUCAGUCAUUGCUGUCUACCUCCAGCCCAAAAAUCCGUAUGCCCAAGGGAGGGGCAAGUUCUUUGGUCUCUUCUAUGCAGUGGGCACUCCUUCACUUAACCCUCUCGUAUACACCCUGAGGAACAAGGAGAUAAAGCGAGCACUCAGGAGGUUACUAGGGAAGGAAAGAGACUCCAGGGAAAGCUGGAGAGCUGCUUAAUAUACUUUCGAAAGUAAGAAGAGUUUCUUCAAGAUUUAUGAACAUGUUAAGUUUUCCAGACUACUACCCUUCCCACAUACACCUGAGCCACUGUGGUGGGUCACAGUGUGGCUAUGUUAUCUAUGAGAGGGAGAAUGAGAAAGAGAGGGACAGAGAGAUAAAAGAAAUUGGGUGAGAGGAGAUAGGUAGCUCCAUAAGGCACACAAAUUCAAAUAUUAUCAUUCCUAUCACUGUCCAUUCUUAAUAUUUCUAUCCUCCAUUCUGUUCUUUUUACUGUCAUCACUUCUAUAGAUUUCCUAACUCCACCAUGCCUAUUUCUGGUUAUAUAAUUGCUCUCCAAUUGUCAUGUCAGUGUAGGGGAACUACUCCAUCAUAGCAUUCUGGACACCUUGCAUGUAUCUACGUAGGUCAUGUAAGCAAAGGCUUGAAGAACAGCUAAUCUGAGAUUUAGAAGAAUGCUUUUUGAUCCUCCUGGAAUAUGAGAGGAUGGGAGGCCCUUUAGAACCUGCCUCAAUGCCAUCUCUCACUCUCCUUCUUAUAUCCCUGGGAGUAUGUCAUGUGACAAGUCUUUACUGUCUCCCAGGUUUUGGAUGGAGCAUGGGGUUUUCUGCCCCACACCCUUUAGGAUAUAGCUGAAGAAUAUAAUGAGGAAUAGCUGGAUUCUAGAACUGACUCCUCACCAGUGGUAUAUUCCACAACAGUGUCACAGUCGUCUGGCCCCUUUGGUUUCCGUGUCAUCCUUUUUGGUGUGUAGGACAAGGAGCCAGGGAAUUGGCACGUUUGGCUUUUACUUCUUUUUUAUAUGUAAAUAAUAAGCCAUCUAAGUGUAAAAGUGGCUCAUAUCUUCUCCAGCCAAAUCAGCUAGGCCAUGGCCUUGCCUUGCUUCUCAUGAGUGUGCUUGACAGUCAUCACCGUCACUCUAUCUUCAUUUCUGGUUCUUACCGUGUUAGCUUAGUUCAUUCAAGCUACUAUCACAAGCUACACAUAAAUUGGGUGGUUUAUAAAUAACAAACAUUUCUUUCUUACAGUUCUGGAGGCUGGAAACUCCAAGAUUAAGGCAGAUUUCAUGCCUAUUGAGGGCCUGCUUUCUGAUUAUAGAAGGUGACUUCUUGCUGUGCCCACACAUGGUGAAAGGGACUACCAACUCUCUGGAGUCUCUUUUAUGAGGGCACUAAUUCCAAUUAUGAAGCCUCUUCCCUCGUGACCUAAUCACUGCCCAAAGGCCCCAUGUUCUAAUGCCAUCAUCUUGGUGGUUUAGGAUUUCAACAUAUGAAUUUUGGAAGGACAUAAGCAUUCAACCCCCUGCACAUGUCUUCUUUCCUACUUCCUCAAGGUUCUUUCUGUCCAGUUGCUCCUUCUUCUAUUGACCCUUUUUUGCCUUCUCUUUCUCCUUCACUGCCUCAAGUUACAGCCAGAGGAAAGGAGGAACUAAAACUUAGCAAAUCUAUAAUCACAUGCAAAUACACAGAAUGGAUUGUUACAACCAAAAUGCAGGCUCUAUUGUUUUCAAUUUAGCAGCCUUUCAAAUGUAUAUGGUUCUGGCCACAUUAAAGUUGCAAAUAACACUUUUUUUGAGACUGAAAUAAAGGUGAAAUAUUGGAA